CUCUCUGUAGCCGCCCGCGGAGCAUCGCAGCCGGCCCGGGCCCCCGCCAGCCUCCCUCCUCGCGUCCCUCGGUGUCCUCCGCGGGCCGGCGCGAUGCGGCUGGGCCCGAGGACCGCGGCGUUGGGGCUGCUGCUGCUGUGCGCCGCCGCGGCCGGCGCCGGCAAGGCCGAGGAGCUGCACUACCCGCUGGGCGAGCGCCGCAGCGACUACGACCGCGAGGCGCUGCUGGGCGUCCAGGAAGAUGUGGAUGAAUAUGUUAAACUCGGCCACGAAGAGCAGCAAAAAAGACUGCAGGCGAUCAUAAAGAAAAUCGACUUGGACUCAGAUGGCUUUCUCACUGAAAGUGAACUCAGUUCAUGGAUUCAGAUGUCUUUUAAGCAUUAUGCUAUGCAAGAAGCAAAACAACAGUUUGUUGAAUAUGAUAAAAACAGUGAUGAUACUGUGACUUGGGAUGAAUAUAACAUUCAGAUGUAUGAUCGUGUGAUUGACUUUGAUGAGAACACUGCUCUGGAUGAUGCAGAAGAGGAGUCCUUUAGGAAGGAAUUUGCCAUUUGUAAAAAACAGUCUUUCUGUUUUUGGCUUCUUCGAUUUAAUCUUCACUUAAAGGACAAGAAGCGAUUUGAAAAAGCUAACCAGGAUUCAGGUCCCGGUUUGAGUCUUGAAGAAUUUAUUGCUUUUGAGCAUCCUGAAGAAGUUGAUUAUAUGACGGAAUUUGUCAUUCAAGAAGCUUUAGAAGAACAUGACAAAAAUGGUGAUGGAUUUGUUAGUUUGGAAGAAUUUCUUGGUGAUUACAGGUGGGAUCCAACUGCAAAUGAAGAUCCAGAAUGGAUACUUGUUGAGAAAGACAGAUUCGUGAAUGAUUAUGACAAAGAUAACGAUGGCAGGCUUGAUCCCCAAGAGCUGUUACCUUGGGUAGUACCUAAUAAUCAGGGCAUUGCACAAGAGGAGGCGCUUCAUCUAAUUGAUGAAAUGGAUUUGAAUGGUGACAAAAAGCUCUCUGAAGAAGAGAUUCUGGAAAACCCGGACUUGUUUCUCACCAGUGAAGCCACAGAUUAUGGCAGACAGCUCCAUGAUGACUAUUUCUAUCAUGAUGAGCUUUAAUCUCUGAGCCUGUCUCAGUAGAGUACUGGCUCCUUUUAUAAUUUGUUACCAGCUUUACUUUUGUGAUAAAAUAUUGAUGUUGUAUUUUACACUCUUAAGUCUUAACCACAGUCAGAAUUAUCUUAAUGUAGAUUAUAAUUUUGGUCUUUUAGGAAAAAAAAACAAAAAUCUGAUAUUUAUUUCAAAAUGUAUUGAAGCAACAAAAUAUUAAUAUUGUGCCAUAUGACAACAAAGUCUUUCCUAAAUACUCCAUCUGUUUAGUACUGUAUUGUGGAAUAUUUGAGUUCUAUUUCCAUACUUGAAAACAUGGAGGAUUUUAGAGAUGCCUGAACAAUAUUAUUUAAGUAGUAUGUGACCGAGCUAUAAAUUUUUGUUUUUGUUCUAAGUAGAUUUAAUUUGGGAACUGACAGGACAAUGUUUUUAGGUUUAGCAUUUUGUUUAAAAACCUUUAAAGAAACCUUUAGAAGGACUUAGACCUCACAUAUUAAUGUUGAGAAGUUCUGCUUAAUUUUAAAAUGGUUUCUAUAAAGGGUUUUAUUGUAUGAAAUAGAACUUUAUAUUUUUGCAUAUGUAUAGAUAGUAAUUAUAUUUAAUGUAUAACUAUAGCAUUAUGGUGAGUGGAAUUUGACAUUGUCCAAACCUUUUUCAUUUUUGAGUGAUUAAAAAUGAAAUGUCCUUUGUAUAUGUUUGUUUGCUUUUCUUUAACUUUCAGAUAAAUAUUGAAUUUAGCAUAGGUUUUGUGGUAUUGUACAUUAUCUUGCCUCAUCCAUUCCUUUAUGUGGAUAGUUCCCAAAACUGUCAAAUUAUUCUUGCUGCAUUUUCUUAUUUUUUUUUUAAAUAAGAGAAUCAUGUUAUAAUAUAAUUGAAUGUGCACCUGACACAUUUUAAUAAUUGGUGUUGUAGCAAAUGUGGUUUUGCUCUUUGGGGCUAUAAAUAAUCUUGAGUAACGCAGGUUGGAAUUACCAAUAGAGCUGGUCAGUUAUCAACAGUAGAGCUCAGUAUCAAUUUUACUGAAAUUAAAAUCAUACUUGAUAAGCAUGAUAAUCAAUUUUAACCUAAUUCAGCAGGUCAACUUAUUUAACUUUGGUGGAGGUGGGAUAGGGAAAAGUGAAGGGAGGAAUUAAUUUUUUUCUAGUUCUGAUGUACAGAGAUUGUUUUUCAUUCUUUUUUUUUUUUUUUUUUUUGUGACAGAGUCUUGCUCUGUGGCCCAGGCUGGAGUGCAGGGGCACUAUCUCGGCUCACUGCAAGCUCUGCCUCCUGGGUUCACGCCAUUCUCCUGCCUCAGCCUCCCGAGUAGCUGGGACUACAGGCGCCUGCCACCACACCCGGCUAAUUUUUUUGUAUUUUUAGUAGAGACCGGGUUUCACCGUGUUAGCCAGGAUGGUUUCGAUCUCCUGACCUCAUGAUCAGCCCACCUCGGCCUCCCAAGGUGCUGGAAUUACAGGCGUGAGCCAACGCGCACGGCCUCUAGUUUUUCAUUCUUUAAAUCACUUUUAUUUGUGGGUGAAGAGGUCAGCUAUGCAUUCUCUUAAUCACUUUCCAGCCUAAAGUUGUCUCAUAUACAGCACACUGGGGGCUCAACAAGUACCUAUGACUAUUUGAGAAGACAUGAAACUCUUCUCUGAUAGAAUCGACUGCACCUAUAUACCUCUCUACUGCCGCAUCUUUGCUGAUGUGAGGUGUGCUUGCAAAUUGUAAGCUUCCACACCUUAAUGACUGCUUGCUUGGGUAUCUACAUGGUUUUCAUUUUAACCUACACUAUAUGUCUGGCUAUAGCAGUUUUAGAAUUACAGAUUUACCACUAUCACUCAUCUGUCAUUUGUCAGACUCACUGAAGCUGGCAUAUUUGAAAUCACCAGUUUGACUAGUUAACUAUUUGUUUUUCUCUCUAGCUUCUCCAAAAUCUAUGCCAGAAUAGAUCAUCAGAUAUGGAUUAUAUUUCAAUCCUUUGCAGAAAUGCAAUGUCUGUACUACUUUCCUUCCUAGCAUAAAGAAAACUACACUUCCCAGCCCUCUUGUAGGUAGGCGAUGGCUAGUUCUGACCAGUUAAACAUGGGUGGAAGUAGUGUGUGUCACUAUCAGACUAUCUCAUGACAAACCCUUUUCCUCUGCCACAGCACUGUGCAGGAGGCCUCAGCUGAAAUGGUGCAGCCACAAGAUGAAAGUGGCUUUGAUCUUGAGUCUGUGUAGGUCAGCUGGAUCCACAGUGGGCUUUGUAUGAUCAAAAAAUAAGCUUUUAAUUAUGUUAAGCCACUGAGAUUUGGUUGUGCUUUUUUGUUUUUAACCACAGCAGAGCCCAUCCUGCUGUGACUGAGUGAAGAUUUCACAUUUAACAAUAGGCUUUUAAUAAGCAUGCAGAGAAAAAGAAUCAUCUGCUUGAACAGAGAUGCUAUAUCUACUGCUGAGUCAAAAUAGAAAAUUUUAAGGCUUUUUUUAGAUUUGAAUUUUAAAUAAGACUUUUAAAAUAAAGCUUUUAUUUUGGUUUUAAUAUAAUUAGGAUAAUUUGAAUUUAUCCUUGAGCAUGAGAGUAAAAAUAGUUUGAGACUUUCUGAAUCAUUGGCUGAUUCUGCCUGAAGGACUUAAUGACUUCCAUUAUUUGAGUUCAGGUACAACUUCAAAGGGGAAAAUUGAAUGGGAUGUGCACAUGUUGGCUCAUAUGUAGUUCUGAUUGGGCCAAUUUGCAGGACAGAAAAUGAUGUCUAGAUUAUGAUAUAAAUUUAAAGGAAGCCAGGACGUUCAGAGGAAAAGCUAGCAUAUCAUGUUUGCCUUACUUAGUUCUUUCCUUUGCAGUUUUAAAAAUAGGCUUUUUUUUUUUUUAGUGUAGUUUUAUGUUCACAGCAAAAUUGAGCAAAAAGUAGUAUAGAGAGUUUCAAUAUGUCCCCUGCCCCACAUACGUACAGCCUCCCCCACUAUCCUAUCCUAUAUGUCAUGAGAUAGUACCUACCAGAGUGGUACAUUUGUUAAAAUCGAUGAAACUGUUAACAUAUCAUUGUCACCCAAAGUGCAUAGUUUACAUUAGGGUUCACUCUUGGUGCUGCACAUGCUCUGGGUUUGGACAAAUGUAUAAUUACAUAUUCCCACCAUUGUAGUGUGGUAGAAUAUUUCCCUUGCCCUAAAGUCUUUCUGCUCCACCUAUUCAUCCCUCCCUUCCCUGUAACCCCAAGCAAUACUGAUCUUUUUACUGUUCAUAAUUUUUUAGAUUGUAGUAAAAUACACAUAACAAAAUUCAUCUUAACAGUUUUUAAUUGUACAGUUCGGUGGUAUGGUAUUAAAUACAGUCAAAAUGUGAAACUAUUACCACCUUCCAUCUCCAUGAACUUCAUUUGUAAAACGGAAAUUUAUACCCAUUAAACAAUAAAGCCCCCUUUCCCCUUCCCUUCAGCACCUGGCAAACACCAUUCUAGUUUUUUUGUUUGAGAUGGAGUCUUGCUCUUGUUGCCCAGGCUGGAGUGCAAUGGCAUGAUUUCGGCUCACUGCAACCUCUGUCUCUUGGGGUCAAGCGAUUCUCCUGCCUCAGCCUCCCGACUAGGUGGGAUUACAGGCGGGCACCACCAUGCCCCCUAAUUUUUUGUAUUUAGUAGAAAUGGGGUUUCACCAUGUUGGUCAAGCUGGUCUCGAACUCCUGAUCUCAGGUGAUCCACCUGCCUCAGCCUCCCAAAGUGCUGGAAUUACAGGCGUGAGCCACCGUGCCCAGCCUCCCAUUCUAGUUUUCUUUUUCUUUCUUUUUUGAGACGGAGUCUCACUCUUGUCAUCCAGGCUGGAGUGCAGUGGUGCGAUCUCGGCUCACUGCAACCUCCACCUCCCAGGUUCAAGCGAUUCUCCUGCCUCAGCCUCCCAAGUAGCUGGGAUUAUAGAUGCCCGCUACCACGCCCGGCUAAUUUUUGUACUUUUAGUAGAGACGGGGUUUCGCCAUGUUGGCAUGGCUGGUCUCGAACUCUUGACCUCAGGUGAUCCACCUGCCUCGGCCUCCCAAAGUGCUGAGAUUACGGGCAUGAGCCACCGCGCCCAGCCCCAUUCUAGUUUGUGUCUAUUAAAAUAGACUCAUAUAGUAUUUGUCUUUUUGUGAGUGGCUUCACUUAGCAUAACGUCCCCAAAGUUCACCCAUAUUGUUACCAGAAUUUCUUUCGUCAGGCUGAACAAUACUUUAUUGUUUGCAUAUACCACAUUUUGCUUAUCCAUUCACCCUUUGAUGGACACAGGUUGCUUCCACCUUUUAUUGUGAAUAAUGCUGCCAUGAAUAUGGGUGUACAAAUAUUUCUUUGAGAUCCUGCUUUUAGUUCUUUUGGAUAUAUAUUAUACAUAGAAGUGGGAUUGCUGGAUCAUAUAGUAAUUCUAUAUAUAUAUAUAUAUAUAUAUAUAUAUAUAUAUAUAUUUUUUUUUUUUUUUUUUUUUUUUUUUUUUUUGAGACGGAGUCUCGCUCUGUCGCCCAGGCUGGAGUGCAGUGGCGCGAUCUCGGCUCACUGCAGGCUCCGCCUCCCGGGUUCACACCAUUCUCCUGCCUCAGCCUCCCGAGUAGCUGGGACUAUAGGCGCCUGCCACCGCACCCGGCUAAUUUUUUGUAUUUUUAGUAGAGACGGGGUUUCACCGUGUUAGCCAGGAUGGUCUUGAUCUGCUGACCUCGUGAUCCGCCCGCCUUGGCCUCCCAAAGUGCUGGGAUUACAGGCGUGAGCCACCGCGCCCGACUAGUAAUUCUAUUUUUAAUAUUUUGAGGAACUGCCAUAGUGUUUCCCACAGCAGCUGUGCCAUUUUGCAUUUCCACCAAUAGUGCACAAGAGUUCCAGUUUCUUUACAUCCUUACCAACACUUGCUAUUUUCUGUUUUUUUUUUUUUCUUUUUUUUUUUUAAUAGUAGCCAUCCUGUUGGGUGAGACGUGGUAUCUCGUUGUGGCUUUGAUUUGCAUUUCCCUAAUGGUCUGUCUCUACAGUUUUGCCUGUUCCAGAAUAUCAUUCCUUUGCAAUUUAAAUGUGAGGAUAAAUGUAUGCUAUUGUUUCUCAAACGUUUUUGUGUUACAAUACCUCCUUUUGAGUGAGAAAUGUCAACUCAAACUUACACUUUUUCACUUAGGAAGAUGAUUUAGGAAAGCCACUUAGAGUAAAAGUUUUUAAACAACUGUAAAAACUAAUUUGCUUCAUUGCAACAUUUGAGUUCUGUCGAAUAAAUAUUUGGCCAGA